AGUAGGGGCCGACUGGCGGCUGACGCUCCCUGAGUGGCGACUCCGUCUCCAGCCCCGCUGCGGAGCGCGGGCCGGAUCUGGGGCGGCCAGGGCCCGGAGCCGCGGAGCCCUCCCCGCCGCCCGGCCGAGCACGGGACCCCGGCGGGGUGGGCGCAGGGGGCGGCCCCGCUCUGGGCGACUGCCGAGGGGCGGGCGGAGGGCCGGGCUCGGCUGGCGGUGGGGCGGGGGCCGCCGGGACUGGGCGCGCGGCCUGAAGCCAGCCCGGGGGCGGCAGGAGAGGGACGCGCGGCGGCAGCGAGCGCAGGGAACAGCUCCUGCCCAGGUCUGUGGGCACUCAGCAUGGAUUUCAGUCUCCCUGUGAGUGAUGGGAAAGAACUAACAGAGGUGUCAUCCUUGAAGGAUAGAAUAAAUCAGCUGUCGUGUUCUCAGUGAAAAGUGGAAAGAAGUUUUAAAGGAUCUGCAAAAUAGAAUUAUGAGACAGAGGAAAGAAAGAAACAGACAAUCUGAUCUCUAUCUUCAUCGGCCAGGAACCCUGUUUCUAUUUUUAUUUUAGGAACCCUGUUUACAUCUUCUUAAAAGUUGGUCUCACUCGUUGCUCAGGCUGGAGUACAGUGGUGCCAUCACAGUAUACUGCAACCUCCACCUCCUGGGCUCAGGUGGACGUCUGAUUUAUGAAGCUCCCCAUCCACCUAUCUGAGUACCUGACUUCUCAGGACUGACACCUACAGCAUCAGGUACACAGCUUCUCCUAGCAUGACUUCGAUCUGAUCAGCAAACAAGAAAAUUUGUCUCCCGUAGUUCUGGGGCGUGUUCACCACCUACAACCACAGAGCUGUCAUGGCUGCCAUCUCUACUUCCAUCCCUGUAAUUUCACAGCCCCAGUUCACAGCCAUGAAUGAACCACAGUGCUUCUACAACGAGUCCAUUGCCUUCUUUUAUAACCGAAGUGGAAAGCAUCUUGCCACAGAAUGGAACACAGUCAGCAAGCUGGUGAUGGGACUUGGAAUCACUGUUUGUAUCUUCAUCAUGUUGGCCAACCUAUUGGUCAUGGUGGCAAUCUAUGUCAACCGCCGCUUCCAUUUUCCUAUUUAUUACCUAAUGGCUAAUCUGGCUGCUGCAGACUUCUUUGCUGGGUUGGCCUACUUCUAUCUCAUGUUCAACACAGGACCCAAUACUCGGAGACUGACUGUUAGCACAUGGCUCCUUCGUCAGGGCCUCAUUGACACCAGCCUGACGGCAUCUGUGGCCAACUUACUGGCUAUUGCAAUCGAGAGGCACAUUACGGUUUUCCGCAUGCAGCUCCACACACGGAUGAGCAACCGGCGGGUAGUGGUGGUCAUUGUGGUCAUCUGGACUAUGGCCAUCGUUAUGGGUGCUAUACCCAGUGUGGGCUGGAACUGUAUCUGUGAUAUUGAAAAUUGUUCCAACAUGGCACCCCUCUACAGUGACUCUUACUUAGUCUUCUGGGCCAUUUUCAACUUGGUGACCUUUGUGGUAAUGGUGGUUCUCUAUGCUCACAUCUUUGGCUAUGUUCGCCAGAGGACUAUGAGAAUGUCUCGGCAUAGUUCUGGACCCCGGCGGAAUCGGGAUACCAUGAUGAGUCUUCUGAAGACUGUGGUCAUUGUGCUUGGGGCCUUUAUCAUCUGCUGGACUCCUGGAUUGGUUUUGUUACUUCUAGACGUGUGCUGUCCACAGUGCGACGUGCUGGCCUAUGAGAAAUUCUUCCUUCUCCUUGCUGAAUUCAACUCUGCCAUGAACCCCAUCAUUUACUCCUACCGCGACAAAGAAAUGAGCGCCACCUUUAGGCAGAUCCUCUGCUGCCAGCGCAGUGAGAACCCCACCGGCCCCACAGAAGGCUCAGACCGCUCGGCUUCCUCCCUCAACCACACCAUCUUGGCUGGAGUUCACAGCAAUGACCACUCUGUGGUUUAGAACGGAAACUGAGAUGAGGAACCAGCCGUCCUCUCUUGGAGGAUAAACAGCCUCCCCCUACCCAAUUGCCAGGGCAAGGUGGGGUGUGAGAGAGGAGAAAAGUCAACUCAUGUACUUAAACACUAACCAAUGACAGUAUUUGUUCCUGGACCCCACAAGACUUGAUAUAUAUUGAAAAUUAGCUUAUGUGACAACCCUCAUCUUGAUCCCCAUCCCUUCUGAAAGUAGGAAGUUGGAGCUCUUGCAAUGGAAUUCAAGAACAGACUCUGGAGUGUCCAUUUAGACUACACUAACUAGACUUUUAAAAGAUUUUGUGUGGUUUGGUGCAAGUCAGAAUAAAUUCUGGCUAGUUGAAUCCACAACUUCAUUUAUAUACAGGCUUCCCUUUUUUAUUUUUAAAGGAUACGUUUCACUUAAUAAACACGUUUAUGCCUAUCAGCAUGUUUGUGAUGGAUGAGACUAUGGACUGCUUUUAAACUACCAUAAUUCCAUUUUUUCCCUUACAUAGGAAAACUGUAAGUUGGAAUUAUCUUUUGUUUAGAAAGCAUGCAUGUAAUGUAUGUAUGCAGUAUGCCUUACUUAAAAAGAUUAAAAGGAUACUAAUGUUAAAUCUUCUAGGAAAUAGAACCUAGACUUCAAAGCCAGUAUUUGUUUAGGUCAUGAAGCAAACAAUGCUCUAAUCACAAUAUUAACUGUUUAAUUAAAAUGUUGUAACAAGUAUAAAACAGGGAAUGUAAGUUUAUUACCAAAGUGAUAUGUAUUCCAAAAAAGUCAUAGAAGAUGAAGCACUAUAAUAUUGUUCCCAUAUAUUUAAAAUACCCAAGUACAUUCUAAUUACCAGUAUAUCAGAGGAAAAUUUUCGUAGUCUUUGUAAAAUAAUAUACUCAUCAUAGAAAACUUGAAAAAUGCAGAAAUGUAUAAAAAAGCAAAAAUGAUUACUGAUAAUAUCACAACCCAGAAGUAACCACCUUUAAAAAGCAACCCCCAUGUAUGCCUAUAUGUGUAUUGUAUACUUUUUUUACAUAAUUGGAGUCAUACUGUAAACAGUUUUAUAAGUAGAUCUUUUUCAUUGCAAAAUUGCCACAUUUUCUUAUGGCAUUAAAAAUUUUACAAAAACAUAAUUUUAAUGGCUAUAUUAUAUUCCAUUUAAUGGAUGCAACUCAGUUUAUUUAACCAUUCCCAUGUUGUUAACUAUUUAGGUUGUUUCUAAUUUUCAUUAUUAUAAAGUUGCAGAAAUUUGGUGUACAUAAAACUGUCUCCAUAUAAUUGAUUAUUAGGAUAUAUUCCCAUGAAGGAUUCUUUUUUUAAAAAAAUGUGAAAUGUCAUCUUGUACUUACACCUUUCAUGAAAAGGGAUUUCCUGCUUUUGUACUGCAUGGGUGGCAGUUGUGAGGAAAAGCCAGUCAAAUGACCUUUUUACAAAAGAAAUGCAGUGGUCACUUCAGUUGAGAGUGACUUUUUAAUACAACAAGAUCAACUAGAAGAAUUCAACUGUCUCAAGAAUCAAGGUACCCCAAUAUAUCUCGCAAUUCCAAACUUUGUUUGAGGGACUCGUUAUCCAGCUCUUGGUAGCCACACCUGCAAUGUAAAAUGGAAGAAAAUGCAAAGAAACCAAAUGUGCCGAGUGAAUAAAGGAUUGUCAUAUCAAUUAGUGUGGGUCCAUCUGUAGCAAAUGGGUUGAGUGUGUCAGUAUGUGGUUGGUUACUGUGUAUUCGCCAGGAAUCACCCCGAUAGGCUGCCACCCUAUUAGGUGAUACCUGUUUAAUAUGUUGUCCAGGUAGACUAGUAGUUGCAUCAGUUUGCUGUAACAAGUAACCAGUGAGGUAACACAGUGGUGAAGCAGGUCAGGGGAGGUCAGGAGGAUGUCUGAGAGAAAGAAGUCCGGGAGAUGAAUGGCUGUCUAGGAAGGAGGAUGUCAGUGCACGGUUAGUGUUUGAGCAGAGGGCAGACUUGUAAAGUACCUGUAGUGAAAAGAAUGUGGGGACCCGAUUAGCAGAAAGGUGUUUGCACGUACUUUAUACAAAAUACAGAAUACUUUAUAUUGGAAGUGAAAGAAAUGAACGUGGACUUUUACACAUGUGCAUAUUUUUCUGGAGGCUAUAUGGAUUAUUUGAAAUGAAAAGCAUACUAAUUGGACUUUAAUAAAUCAUUUUCAAUCA